AGCCCGUGCUCGCCGGUGUCGGGUCCUAAGUCCCUCGGUCUUGGGUUCCCGGAGAGGUGAGUCGGCUGCAGGUGGGUGCGGGGCGCCGGGCUGUUCGGGGUACCGGUGUCGCAGUCGCCAGUCCGAGCUCACACCGGGCGUGGAGUUCAGCUGCGCAUCGGGUUGCGGCAGCUUCGCCAGGCCUGGGGCUGGCUGGGCCGCGGGGCCGCCCUGGAGGCCGGAGCCACUGGGCCUGCGGCGCCUCGGCAGCGAGCAGCCGCUUUGCUCGCGUGCAGGAGGCUGUUCGCUACCUCACACCCCCGGCUGGCGCUGUGGCCUCGCUUAGCUCUACCGUUUAGCACCCGGCGACAUGCACCCGGUCGGUUUCCGCCAGGAUGCGGGAGAGUUGGGGCAAGCUACCUGCGACAGCUUGAACUUUUCCUAGGGAUUCCGCUCCACCCGCCGGUUAGAGCGUAUUGCUCAUUAAAUCCGAGACCUGUGUGCUUGCUACUGAAAUAAAAGAAGUAUUUUUUCCCCAGAGUCCUUUUAGGACGUUAUGACUUUUCUCCUUUGCAAGACUGCAAAAAACUGACAAGAAGACAAAACUCUUCCCACUCCCAGGGACCGCGUUGUCUUGAGUUUGGCUAGUAAAGGCUAGCAAGUGAGGCUUUGUCUCUGCAUCCCGUUCCCCCUAACAUCCUCAGAGAACCUUCGUUUCUAGAAUCUUUCUAGUAUUCAGAGACUUCUCCAGGGUCAUGAUCCCAAAGGCUUAACCCGUUUACAAGGAGAGAGUUGUCUCCUGACGCCCAAAAUGGCAGCUAAAAUGGAGAUAACUUUAAGCUCCAACACUGAAGCUUCCUCCAAGCAAGAGAGACACAUAAUAGCCAAACUAGAAGAGAAACGGGGCCCUCCUCUGCAAAAAAACUGCCCAGAUCCUGAGCUCUGCCGCCAGAGCUUCAGACGCUUUUGUUAUCAAGAGGUGUCUGGACCCCAAGAGGCUCUCUCCCAGCUCCGACAGCUCUGCCGUCAGUGGUUGCAACCCGAGCUGCACACCAAGGAGCAGAUUUUGGAGCUUCUGGUGAUGGAGCAGUUCCUGACCAUCCUGCCCCCGGAGAUCCAGGCUCGGGUCAGGCAUCGAUGUCCAAUGAGCAGCAAGGAGAUUGUGACCCUCGUGGAAGAUUUUCACAGAGCAUCCAAGAAACCAAAGCAGUGGGUGGCCGUUUGUAUGCAGGGGCAAAAGGUGCUCUUGGAGAAAACUGGAUCUCAGCUUGGAGAACAGGAACUGCCAGACUUUCAACCGCAGACUCCUAGGAGAGAUCUCAGGGAGAGCUCUCCAGCAGAGCCUUCCCAGGCAGGAGCUUAUGACCGGCUGAGCCCCCAUCAUUGGGAGAAAUCCCCACUCCUCCAAGAACCAACCCCCAAAUUGGCUGGGACAGGUAAACACUCUGCCUUUUCUCUCCCUCUCAUCAGCCCUUUAUCUCCAUCAAUGUAUCUCAUGGUUCUGCAAAGGCAUAGACCACAUGUGUGUGUUUUUUUAAAUGUUAUAUAUAAUAGUAGAUGAUUAUUCACUAAACAAAUUUCACUAAUUAGGAUGGUGGUGAUACUACAAGUAAGUAUGUUUUUAUCGUUUUCUGUUAAUGAAAAUUUAAGAAUCCAGUGCAUGACAGGGUUGUACCUACUUUUCUGUCCGUUUCAGAACUUCUUAUAGAAAAGACAGAUCCAAAUAUGGCCACAGAUGAACUUCCAUGCAAGCUAUGGCUGAGUUUCAUUGCUUAAAAUGCUCCUCUGUUUAGAGGGGCCUGGUAGAAAUAAAAACCCACCCUAUAUCUUAUAUCUUUGUCCUCCUCUGUGAUGUUGCUUGUACUUUAGAUCCUCAAAUCUAUUUCCCUUUCUCUGGUGUGAUACUUGUGUAACUGCUGGCCUUGUUCUACACAGUCCUGUGAUCUCUAAGCCUGAAUGACAGUGACAUUUUGGCCAAGCCUGGUGAUGUGAAUACAAGAUACAGUGAGCACGUUAGGGAGGAGGGUUACAAGACGACAAAAAUCCUCAGUUUCUUAAUAUUUGCUACAUCCAAUGAGGUACUUCGUGUUUUAGUCUGUUCAGGCUGCUAAUAUAAAAUGCUAGAGACUAGGUAGUUUAUAAACAACAGGAGUUUAUUUCUCACAGUUCUAGAGGCUAGGAAGUCUGAGUUCAAGGUGCCAGCAUGGUUGGGUUCCAGUGAGGCCCCUCUUCCAGGUCACAGACUGCCUACUUCUCAGUCCUCAUGUGGCAGAAGGGGAAGACAGGCUCCCGUGGGGCUCUUUCAUGAAGGCACUAAUCCCAUUCCAGUGAGGGCAGCACCCUCAUGACCUAAUCACCUCCCAAAGGCCCCAUGUCCUAACACUAUUACCUUGGGAGUUAGAAUUUCAUAUGAAUUUGGAGGAACAUAAACAUUUAGCCCCUGGCAACCACAGUCUACUUUUUGUCUCUAGAAUUGCUUAUUCUGAACAUUUUAUACAAAUGGAAUCACACAGGCCGGGCACAGUGGCUCACGCCUGUAAUCCCAGCACUUUGGGAGGCCAAGGCAGGCGGAUCACUUAGGCUCAGGAGUUCGAGACCAGCCUGGGCAACAUGGCGAAAUCCUGUCUCUACAAAAAAUGCAAAAAUUAGCGGGGCAUGGUGCUGCACACCUGUAAUCCCAGCUGCUUGGGGGAGCUGAGGCAGGAGGAUCACUUCAACCUGGGAGGUCGAGGCUGCAGUGAACUGAGAUCGUGCCACUGCACUCUAGCCUAUGUGACAAAGUAAGACCCUGUCUCAAAAAUAAAUAAAUAAAUAAAUUGAAUCACACAA